GACAGAUCGCCCGGGUGGGUGCAAGAUGGCGCAAGCGGCGCUCCCCCUGCGCCCCCCGCGCUGCUGAGCAGGCAUGCGGCCCCAGUCCCCCACCGCCUGGGCUCGGCCCCGGCCGGAGCCCCAGCCCCGGCCCCGGCGCCGGCCCCGCGGGACGCUGUGAGCCGCGAGAGGCCCGGGAGCCGCGCGUCGCCGAGCCGAGCUGACCGAGAGCCCCAUGGCUGUGCAGCGCGCCGCGUCUCCGCGCCGCCCGCCCGCCCCGCUCUGGCCCCGGCUCCUGCUGCCGCUGCUGUUGCUGCUGCUGCCCGCGCCGAGCGAGGGUCUUGGCCACUCUGCUGAACUGGCAUUUGCUGUGGAGCCAAGUGAUGAUGUUGCCGUCCCCGGGCAGCCUAUAGUGCUGGACUGCAGGGUGGAGGGGACCCCUCCAGUGCGAAUCACCUGGAGGAAGAAUGGGGUAGAGCUGCCAGAGAGUACCCACUCCACCUUGCUGGCCAAUGGGUCCUUGAUGAUCCGUCACUUCAGGCUGGAGCCGGGAGGCAGCCCUUCGGAUGAAGGUGACUAUGAGUGUGUGGCCCAGAACCGCUUUGGGCUGGUGGUCAGCCGGAAGGCUCGCAUCCAAGCUGCAACCAUGUCGGACUUCCACGUGCAUCCCCAGGCCACCGUGGGUGAGGAGGGUGGUGUGGCCCGCUUCCAGUGCCAAAUCCAUGGGCUUCCCAAACCCCUGAUCACUUGGGAGAAGAACAGAGUCCCAAUUGACACGGACAAUGAGAGGUACACAUUGCUGCCCAAGGGGGUCCUGCAGAUCACAGGACUUCGAGCUGAGGACGGUGGCAUCUUCCACUGUGUGGCCUCAAACAUCGCCAGUAUCCGGAUCAGCCACGGGGCCAGGCUCACUGUGUCAGGCUCGGGCUCUGGGGCCUACAAGGAGCCAGCCAUCCUCGUGGGGCCUGAGAACCUCACCCUGACAGUGCACCAGACCGCGGUGCUUGAGUGUGUCGCCACGGGCAACCCGCGCCCCAUUGUGUCCUGGAGCCGCCUGGAUGGUCGCCCUAUCGGGGUGGAGGGCAUCCAGGUGCUGGGCACAGGAAACCUCAUCAUCUCAGACGUGACGGUCCAGCACUCUGGCGUCUACGUCUGUGCAGCCAACAGACCUGGCACCCGGGUGAGGAGAACGGCACAGGGCCGGCUGGUGGUGCAAGCCCCAGCUGAGUUUGUGCAGCAUCCCCAGUCCAUCUCCAGGCCAGCUGGGACCACAGCCAUGUUCACCUGCCAAGCCCAGGGUGAGCCACCGCCUCAUGUCACGUGGCUGAAAAAUGGACAGGUGCUGGGGCCAGGAGGCCACGUCAGGCUCAAGAAUAACAACAGCACACUGACCAUUUCUGGAAUCGGUCCUGAGGAUGAAGCCAUUUAUCAGUGUGUGGCCGAGAACAGUGCGGGCUCAUCACAGGCCAGUGCCAGGCUGACCGUACUGUGGGCUGAGGGGCUCCCCGGGCCUCCCCGCAAUGUGCGGGCAGUCUCUGUGUCUUCCACUGAGGUGCGUGUGUCCUGGAGUGAGCCGCUGGCCAACACCAAGGAGAUCAUCGGCUACGUCCUGCACAUCAGGAAGGCUGCUGACCCACCGGAGCUGGAGUAUCAGGAGGCAGUCAGCAAGAGCACCUUUCAGCACCUGGUCAGCGACCUGGAGCCCUCCACAGCCUACAGUUUCUACAUCAAGGCCUACACACCAAGGGGGGCCAGCUCAGCCUCUGUGCCCACCCUAGCUAGCACCCUGGGUGAAGCCCCUGCCCCACCCCCACUGUCAGUGCGAGUCCUGGGCAGCUCCUCCUUGCAGCUGCUGUGGGAGCCUUGGCCCCGGCUGGCCCAGCACGAGGGCGGCUUCAAGCUGUUUUACCGCCCAGCAAGCAAGACCUCCUUCACCGGCCCCAUCCUGCUGCCUGGAACCGUCUCCUCCUACAACCUCAGCCAGCUCGACCCCACUGCAGUGUAUGAGGUGAAGCUGCUCGCCUACAACCAGCAUGGAGAUGGCAAUGCCACAGUCCGCUUUGUGUCUUUGAGGGGAGCAUCUGAGAGGACAGCCUUGAGCCCACCAUGUGACUGCCGGAAGGAGGAGGCCGCCAACCAGACGUCCACCACAGGCAUCGUCAUCGGCAUCCACAUCGGGGUCACUUGCAUCAUCUUCUGUGUCCUCUUCCUCCUGUUCGGCCAAAGGGGCAGGGUCCUCCUGUGUAAAGAUGUGGAAAACCAGCUGUCCCCUCCACAGGGUCCCCGGAGCCAGAGGGACCCUGGCAUUCUAGCCCUAAAUGGGGCGAGACGGGGACAGCGGGGCCAGCUGGGCCGAGACGAGAAACGUGUGGAUAUGAAGGAGCUGGAGCAGCUGUUCCCCCCGGCCAGCGCAGCAGGGCAGCCGGACCCCAGACCCACACAGGAUCCUGCAGCCCCCGCUCCGUGUGAGGAGACCCAGCUCUCCGUGCUGCCACUUCAGGGGUGCGGCCUGAUGGAGGGGAAGACGACGGAGGCGAAGACCACAGAGGCCACGGCUCCCUGCGCCGGCCUGGCGGCUGCCCCACCACCCCCAGAUGGAGGCCCUGGCCUCCUCAGUGAAGGCCAGGCUUCCAGGCCUGCAGCGGCCCGGGUUACCCAGCCAGCUCACUCGGAACAGUAGCCAGUGUCUGGCAGGCUCCAGAGGGUGGACGGAGCGGGGCCCAUUCUCAGGUCAAAAGCAAGAUUUCUACUGUCAUGUGGGAUUUGGAUGGUCCUGGGGGCUCCCCAGCAUUUCUAUCCUGACUGCCUCUUGGGUUGUCAAAACCCAAGGCAGCCUUGACAGGGACCCCCCGGCCCUAACACCCAUCAGGAGUUGGAGCAGUUCCUGCAGGAGCCUGUUCCUUCCCUGGGCUGACGCCCCCUUGCCUCUGCCUGGUACCCACAUGACUUGGAACUGAACUAACAUUUUUCUUUAAAAAGCAAAACUUAAAAAAAAAAAAAAAGAGGAGAGAGAUAGAGGAAGGUGAAUUAGACUCCAAAAGAUGACCCUGCUGUAGCUGGGCCCUGACACUGUCACCCUCCACCGACUUUGUUUUCUCAGGAUGGAUUUUUGCUGUUUUGGCUCUCAGCACCUACCUCAGCCGGAAUGAAUGUCCUGGGGGGCAGUGGGGCGGUGGCCUCAGCCCCCUUACCCCACAGAGCCCGAAUGCACUCCUACCUCAAGUCCCCUUGCUGGGGACCCCCUCUCCCUUCCCACACUGUUGUCCAGAGUAAAAAAAAAAAAAAAAAAAAAAGCACUUCCCCGUUUCCAGGUGUGAAAGAAAAAAAAAAGCACUUCCCCAUUUCCAGAUGUGAAAGAAAAUGUCUACCUCAAGGCUCGCUGGCUCUGUGGGCUGUGUUGUCACUGGACCUGCCUCCCCGCCCCUCCUGCCCACAGCCCACCUACCUCUCCUGCAGAGGAGAGGCCAGAGGUUGGGCCACCAAGGGGAACUCUUGUGGCCUACAGAAAUAGAAAUGGAUUGGGCAGAGAAAAAAUGUGAAAGCAGCCAAAAAUGAGAGGAAAUUUGUUCCUUGAAGUAUAAAUUGUCCAAACGAGCCACCUCCCAGCACACCGCCUGUCCCCGUCUUGUCUGUCCACUCCCAUUUUGAGCCAGCCCAUCCUUGAUGGGGAUGCCCAUGAGGAACCUGGGCUUGGGAGGGUGGCAUCAGCUGGCCGCCUGCCUCCUGUCCUGCAGGCCCGGCCCCUGGAAUGUACCAUGUGUGGGAUGGGUGUGUGGGAGGGUGAGGGGGUGUGGGUGUCCCCUGCAGAGGCGCCCCAGCCUCAGGCACCCAGCCAGCCUGAUCCACCCCUCGACAGGGGAGCAUCCACUGUCAGCAGCCAUGGCCGGAAGCUAUUUUUAUACAAGGUGUGUUAAGGGUUAUGUUCUUGUGACUUUUUGUUACUCUUUUCUGUUGUGUUGUUCUUUGAACUACUUAGUUAAAGAAGAAGAAAAGAAAACCAAGGAAACAAAUACCUAUUUUUGGUUAUACUCAGAAACAUUUUUUUAAAUAGCAGAAGAAAAACUUUUUUUAAAGAAAAAAGAUAAGUGUAUUCCUUAAGAAUGAGACCAUAAAUAUCCCUGACCCCCAAUCCUCUAGGGACACCUCCACCCUGAACUUUAGUUAAUUAGCUGAAGAAGAUAGAAUUUGUGGUGUUUUCCUAGAAAACUAGAGCUGUGUCCGCGUGGACUUGGGGAAGGGUAGUCCCUUCCCUUCUCCCAAAUGAUGUGUGGAUGCCCAGGGCUCCACAAAGCUCCAAGGCAGUGCCCCCUCUGUUCCCAAAGCAGCUUCUCUCGGGAGCCUCCCUCUCCCUUGGGAAGGGUGCGGCUGGGGCAGGAGGGGGCUGGGGGGCCACCUGGCCUUACUUGGGUUUUGUCACACUCUGCUCAUUUUGACUGAAUAAAAGUCCUGUUGCCAAAGUGAA